AAGUCGUGCUGCGGAGCCAAAUUUGAAGCAAGCGGAGGCGCGGGGGCGCGUCUACGAAGCCGGACCUGUAGCAGUUUCUUUGGCUGCCUGGGCCCCUUGAGUCCAGCCAUCAUGCCUAUCCGUGCUCUGUGCACUAUCUGCUCCGACUUCUUCGAUCACUCCCGCGACGUGGCCGCCAUCCACUGCGGCCACACCUUCCACUUGCAGUGCCUAAUUCAGUGGUUUGAGACAGCACCAAGUCGGACCUGCCCACAGUGCCGAAUCCAGGUUGGCAAAAGAACCAUUAUCAAUAAGCUCUUCUUUGAUCUUGCCCAGGAGGAGGAGAAUGUCUUGGAUGCAGAAUUCUUAAAGAAUGAACUGGACAAUGUCAGAGCCCAGCUUUCCCAGAAAGACAAGGAGAAACGAGACAGCCAGGUCAUCAUCGACACUCUGCGGGAUACGCUGGAAGAACGCAAUGCUACUGUGGUAUCUCUGCAGCAGGCCUUGGGCAAGGCCGAGAUGCUGUGCUCCACACUGAAAAAGCAGAUGAAGUACUUAGAGCAGCAGCAGGAUGAGACCAAACAAGCACAAGAGGAGGCCCGCCGGCUCAGGAGCAAGAUGAAGACCAUGGAGCAGAUUGAGCUUCUACUCCAGAGCCAGCGCCCUGAGGUGGAGGAGAUGAUCCGAGACAUGGGUGUGGGACAGUCAGCGGUGGAACAGCUGGCUGUGUACUGUGUGUCUCUCAAGAAAGAGUACGAGAAUCUAAAAGAGGCACGGAAGGCCUCAGGGGAGGUGGCUGACAAGCUGAGGAAGGAUUUGUUUUCCUCCAGAAGCAAGUUGCAGACAGUCUACUCUGAAUUGGAUCAGGCCAAGUUAGAACUGAAGUCAGCCCAGAAGGACUUACAGAGUGCUGACAAGGAAAUCAUGAGCCUGAAAAAGAAGCUAACGAUGCUGCAGGAAACCUUGAACCUGCCACCAGUGGCCAGUGAGACUGUCGACCGCCUGGUUUUAGAGAGCCCAGCCCCUGUGGAGGUGAAUCUGAAGCUCCGCCGGCCAUCCUUCCGUGAUGAUAUUGAUCUCAAUGCUACCUUUGAUGUGGAUACUCCCCCAGCCCGGCCCUCCAGCUCCCAGCAUGGUUACUACGAAAAACUUUGCCUAGAGAAGUCACACUCCCCAAUUCAGGAUGUCCCCAAGAAGAUAUGCAAAGGCCCCAGGAAGGAGUCCCAGCUCUCACUGGGUGGCCAGAGCUGUGCAGGAGAGCCAGAUGAGGAACUGGUUGGUGCCUUCCCUAUUUUUGUCCGGAAUGCCAUCCUAGGCCAGAAACAGCCCAAGAGGCCCAGGUCAGAGUCCUCUUGCAGCAAAGAUGUGGUAAGGACAGGCUUCGAUGGGCUCGGUGGCCGGACAAAAUUCAUCCAGCCUACUGACACAGUCAUGAUCCGCCCAUUGCCUGUUAAGCCCAAGACCAAGGUUAAGCAGAGGGUGAGGGUGAAGACAGUGCCUUCUCUCUUCCAGGCCAAGCUGGACACCUUCCUGUGGUCGUGAGAACAGUGAGUCUGACCAAUGGCCAGACACAUGCCUGCAACUUGUAGGUCAAGGACUGUCCAGGCAGGGGUUUUGUGGACAGAGCCCCACUUUCGGGACCAGCCUGAGGUGUAAGGGCAGACAAACAGGUGAGGGUGAGUGUGGCACCCAGAGACUGCUCUUCCUGCCCUCACCCUGCCCCACUCCUACGACUGGGAGCUGACAUGACCAGCCCACUGAUCCUGUCAGCAGGUCCUGCUCCUGUUGCCAGGCUCCUGUUUAUAGCCAUGAUCAGAUGUGGUCAGACUCUUUCUGGGCCUGGAGACCACGGUCACUUGUUGACUGUCUCUGUGGACCAGAGUGCUUGAGGCAUCUCAGGCAGCCUCAGCCCAAGCUUCUACCUGCCUUUGACUUGCUUCUAGGCAUAGCCUGGGCCAAGCAGGGUGGGGAAUGGAGGAUAGCAUGGGAUGUAUGGAGAGGAUGGAAGAUUUUCAUGUAAAAUAAAAUUAAAAAAAAAAAACAA